AUUGAAGGUGGAGAAGCGCGCGCCGCCGGGGAGCCCCGGCUGCGCCGCGAGGGCGAGGCUGCAAGGCGGCAGGCGGUGGUCGCGCUGGGCGACGGGACGGCGCUGGUUUUUCUCUUGAGUUUUAAAUUGAGGCGGUGGAGGAGGGAGUGGGAGACCCACUCACCCGAUAUGCGCUCUGGUCUCCAUUUCUCCCCACGCUCGCGCCGUUCCUUCGAGUGAGGGAGGGACUCGCAGCGCCGCCCGCGCACCGGACCCACAAGGCGAGCCCCGUGGUGGCGGGGAUGGUUCUGCGCGCCUGGCAGCUCCCACCCCGGUCUCUCCGGCCCGAAGCUGGGGGGCGCAGGGGCUGAGCUGCGCUGCCUCUCGGGGAUCCGCCGCGGGCCGCCUGGGGGCUGGAGGGCGAGACCCGGAGCCCGCCGGGCAGCUCCGAGAGCCGGGGCCGAGGCCAGAGCGCGGCAGCCUGCGUGGGCAGCGGAGACGAGGCCGGGCAAAGGAGACGCGGUGGCUUCAGAGGGGCUUCCAAGUAGAAAACUCCCCGGCCGCCCCCAAACGACGCCCCGGGAGCCAGGCGGGAGCACAGCACGCCCUUCUUGCCCCCUUUGCUCGCCGCGCCGCCUCCCAGGACCCUCCCAAAGCGUCCCUCUCCAAGGCCCCGGCAUCAGCUACCCCUGAAGAAGCCGCCGCCGCUGCCGGAUCCAGGAUUCACACUAAAUGGGCCGGCCGCAGGGGGCCGGGCGCCGGGCUAGGUGGCCGCCAAGAGCCUGGUGAGGGGCUACCCAGAGCCCGGUGGGCGAGGGGCGGCCAAGAGCCCCGGGAGCGUGCCCUCGGGGCGGAGAGCGUCGCGGCCCGCGCCGAGGCGAUGCUCGGGUGGCUGCGAGCUGCCGGCGGCGAGAGGCCAUAGACGGGCAUGGGCCUUGCGUCCCACCACCCCUAGGGACCCUCGAGCCUCGCCCCUCUGCUCCGACUCGCCGGACCGACGCGAUGGCCUCAGAAGUGGUGUGCGGGCUCAUCUUCAGGCUGCUGCUGCCCAUCUGCCUGGCAGUAGCAUGUGCAUUCCGAUACAAUGGGCUCUCCUUUGUCUACCUUAUCUACCUCUUGCUCAUUCCUCUGUUCUCAGAACCAACAAAAACGACGAUGCAAGGACAUACGGGACGGUUAUUAAAGUCUCUGUGCUUCAUCAGUCUUUCCUUCCUGUUGCUGCACAUCAUUUUCCACAUCACGUUGGUGAGCCUUGAAGCUCAACAUCGUAUUGCACCUGGCUACAACUGCUCAACAUGGGAAAAGACAUUCCGGCAGAUCGGCUUUGAAAGCUUAAAGGGAGCUGAUGCUGGCAAUGGGAUCAGAGUGUUUGUACCUGACAUCGGGAUGUUCAUUGCUAGUCUGACCAUCUGGCUCCUCUGUAGAAACAUUGUUCAGAAACCUGUGACAGACGAAGCAGCACAGAGUAACCCGGAGUUUGAAAAUGAAGAAUUGGCUGAAGGAGAAAAAAUUGAUUCAGAAGAGGCACUGAUCUAUGAAGAGGAUUUCAAUGGAGGAGAUGGUGUUGAAGGCGAGUUGGAAGAAAGCACGAAGUUAAAAAUGUUCCGCAGGCUUGCCUCUGUGGCCUCUAAGCUCAAGGAGUUCAUUGGCAACAUGAUCACCACUGCUGGGAAAGUCGUUGUUACCAUCUUACUGGGCUCCUCGGGCAUGAUGUUGCCGUCUUUGACAUCAUCUGUGUAUUUUUUUGUAUUUUUGGGUCUGUGCACCUGGUGGUCCUGGUGCCGGACGUUCGACCCAUUGCUGUUCAGCUGUCUCUGUGUUCUGCUGGCUAUUUUCACUGCUGGACAUUUGAUUGGACUUUAUUUAUACCAGUUCCAAUUCUUUCAAGAGGCAGUUCCACCCAAUGACUACUAUGCAAGGUUGUUUGGUAUCAAGUCAGUAAUUCAAACGGACUGUUCAAGUACUUGGAAGAUCAUAGUGAACCCGGACCUGUCGUGGUACCACCACGCCAACCCUAUCCUCCUGCUGGUGAUGUACUACACUCUGGCCACUCUGAUCCGCAUCUGGCUGCAAGAGCCCCUUGUGCAGGAUGAGGGGACCAAAGAAGAGGACAAAGCCCUGGCUUGUAGCCCCAUCCAAAUAACAGCGGGGAGGAGGCGGAGCCUGUGGUACGCAACCCAUUACCCCACUGAUGAGAGAAAACUUUUAUCCAUGACCCAGGAUGACUACAAACCAUCUGAUGGCCUGCUGGUGACUGUGAACGGCAACCCCGUGGAUUACCACACCAUCCACCCAAGCCUGCCCAUGGAGAACGGCCCUGGCAAAGCCGACCUCUACUCCACCCCUCAGUACCGGUGGGAGCCCUCUGAUGAAUCCUCAGAAAAGCGAGAGGAGGAAGAGGAAGAGAAAGAAGAAUUUGAAGAAGAAAGGAGCCGUGAGGAAAAAAGAAGUAUCAAAGUUCAUGCCAUGGUCUCCGUAUUCCAAUUUAUUAUGAAACAAAGUUACAUCUGUGCCCUCAUAGCUAUGAUGGCCUGGAGCAUCACCUAUCACAGCUGGCUGACCUUCGUGCUGCUGAUCUGGUCGUGCACUCUUUGGAUGAUUCGCAACAGAAGAAAAUAUGCCAUGAUCAGCUCUCCCUUCAUGGUGGUUUAUGGAAACCUAUUGUUGAUAUUACAGUAUAUAUGGAGUUUUGAACUUCCUGAAAUUAAAAAAGUUCCAGGAUUUUUAGAAAAGAAAGAGCCAGGAGAACUUGCUUCCAAAAUCCUUUUCACCAUUACUUUUUGGCUACUGCUGAGGCAGCACCUCACAGAGCAAAAAGCUCUGCAAGAAAAGGAAGCUCUUUUAUCGGAAGUCAAAAUUGGCAGUCAGGAAAAUGAAGAAAAAGAUGAGGAACUUCAAGAUAUACAAGUGGAAGGAGAGCCCAAAGAGGAGGAAGAAGAGGAAGCGAAGGAAGAGAAGCAAGAGAGAAAGAAGGUAGAGCAAGAGGAAGCUGAAGAAGAAGAUGAGCAGGACAUCAUGAAAGUCCUGGGCAAUCUGGUGGUGGCCAUGUUCAUCAAGUACUGGAUCUACGUCUGCGGAGGCAUGUUCUUCUUCGUCAGCUUCGAGGGUAAAAUCGUAAUGUACAAAAUCAUCUACAUGGUGCUGUUCCUGUUCUGUGUGGCCCUAUACCAGGUGCACUAUGAAUGGUGGAGGAAAAUUCUAAAAUAUUUUUGGAUGUCAGUGGUUAUUUACACUAUGCUGGUGCUUAUCUUUAUAUACACAUAUCAGUUUGAGAACUUCCCAGGCCUGUGGCAAAAUAUGACUGGACUGAAAAAAGAAAAGCUUGAGGAUCUUGGCUUAAAGCAGUUUACUGUGGCUGAACUAUUCACUCGCAUAUUCAUCCCAACCUCCUUUCUGCUGGUGUGCAUUUUACACCUGCACUACUUCCAUGACCGGUUCCUUGAACUCACAGACCUCAAGUCCAUUCCCAGCAAAGAAGACAACACCAUCUACAGCCAUGCCAAAGUCAAUGGUCGCGUAUAUCUAAUAAUAAAUAGCAUCAAGAAAAAAUUACCAAUCCACCAAAAUGAACUGGCCCACCCGGAAGGAAGCCUCCCGGACCUCACCAUGAUGCAUCUGACUGCCAGCCUGGAGAAGCCGGAGGUGAGGAAGUUGGCUGAGCCUGGGGAGGAGAAGCUUGAGGGCUACUCUGAAAAAGCCCAGAAGGGUGAUCUUGGGAAAGACAGCGAGGAGUCAGAGGAGGACGGAGAGGAAGAGGAGGAAUCCGAGGAGGAGGAAGAAACAUCAGACUUAAGGAACAAAUGGCACCUGGUGAUUGACCGCCUCACUGUGCUCUUCUUAAAAUUCCUGGAGUAUUUUCACAAGCUGCAGGUGUUCAUGUGGUGGAUUUUGGAGUUGCACAUCAUCAAAAUCGUUUCCUCUUACAUUAUCUGGGUUUCUGUGAAAGAGGUGUCUCUGUUCAACUAUGUAUUUUUGAUUUCUUGGGCUUUUGCUCUGCCGUACGCCAAGCUGCGCCGUCUGGCUUCAAGUGUCUGCACAGUCUGGACGUGUGUGAUCAUCGUCUGCAAAAUGUUGUACCAGCUCCAAACCAUUAAGCCUGAGAACUUCUCUGUUAACUGUUCCUUGCCAAAUGAAAAUCAAACAAACAUCCCCUUUAAUGAGUUGAACAAGUCUCUGCUCUACAGCGCUCCUAUCGAUCCUACAGAGUGGGUCGGCCUGCGGAAGUCUUCGCCUCUGCUAGUCUACCUGAGGAAUAACCUCCUGAUGCUGGCUAUCCUGGCCUUUGAAGUCACCAUUUACCGCCAUCAGGAAUACUAUCGAGGUCGAAAUAACCUGACGGCCCCUGUGUCUAGAACUAUCUUUCAUGACAUUACAAGACUACAUCUAGAUGAUGGACUUAUUAAUUGUGCCAAAUAUUUCAUUAAUUACUUCUUUUACAAGUUUGGUCUGGAGACCUGUUUCCUAAUGUCAGUUAACGUCAUUGGCCAGCGAAUGGAUUUCUAUGCCAUGAUCCACGCCUGCUGGCUGAUCGCUGUCUUAUAUAGACGCAGAAGGAAAGCCAUCGCAGAGAUCUGGCCCAAGUACUGCUGCUUCCUGGCAUGCAUCAUCACCUUCCAGUAUUUCAUCUGCAUUGGCAUCCCACCUGCUCCUUGCCGAGAUUACCCGUGGAGAUUCAAGGGUGCCAGCUUCAAUGACAACAUCAUAAAGUGGCUGUACUUCCCAGAUUUCAUUGUGCGGCCCAACCCUGUGUUUCUCGUCUAUGACUUCAUGCUGCUUCUGUGUGCCUCCUUACAACGGCAGAUUUUUGAGGAUGAGAACAAGGCUGCAGUGCGAAUCAUGGCAGGUGACAAUGUCGAGAUCUGCAUGAACCUUGAUGCGGCCUCCUUCAGCCAACAUAACCCUGUGCCAGAUUUUAUUCACUGCAGAUCUUACUUAGACAUGUCCAAAGUGAUCAUCUUCAGCUACCUCUUCUGGUUUGUGCUCACCAUCAUCUUCAUCACUGGGACCACCAGGAUCAGCAUCUUUUGCAUGGGGUACCUGGUGGCCUGUUUCUACUUCCUGCUCUUUGGGGGCGAUUUGCUGUUGAAACCCAUCAAGAGCAUCCUGCGCUACUGGGACUGGCUGAUCGCAUACAACGUUUUUGUGAUUACGAUGAAAAAUAUCCUGUCAAUAGGAGCAUGUGGAUACAUUGGAACAUUGGUGCACAAUAGUUGUUGGUUGAUCCAGGCUUUCAGCCUGGCCUGCACAGUCAAAGGCUAUCAAAUGCCUGCUGCUAAUUCACCCUGUACACUUCCCAGUGGGGAAGCAGGAAUCAUUUGGGACAGCAUAUGUUUUGCCUUCCUCCUGCUGCAAAGAAGAGUUUUCAUGAGUUAUUAUUUUCUACAUGUUGUGGCUGAUAUAAAAGCUUCCCAGAUUCUGGCAUCAAGAGGAGCUGAACUUUUCCAGGCCACAAUUGUAAAAGCUGUAAAGGCAAGAAUUGAGGAAGAGAAGAAGUCCAUGGACCAGCUGAAGCGACAGAUGGAUCGCAUCAAGGCCAGGCAACAGAAAUAUAAAAAGGGUAAGGAGAGGAUGCUGAGCUUGACCCAGGAGCCAGGGGAAGGCCAGGACAUGCAAAAACUCUCUGAAGAGGAUGAUGAAAGAGAAGCAGACAAACAGAAAGCCAAGGGCAAAAAAAAGCAGUGGUGGCGGCCUUGGGUUGAUCAUGCUUCCAUGGUCAGGAGUGGAGAUUAUUAUUUGUUUGAAACGGAUAGUGAAGAGGAGGAAGAGGAAGAAUUAAAGAAGGAAGAUGAAGAACCUCCACGAAGGUCAGCAUUCCAGAGAGCUAUUGGGAAGUUUGCAUCAGCCAUUUUAGCCUUGCCAAAGUCUGUCAUUAAACUUCCCAAAACUAUUCUUCAGUAUUUAAUCAGAGCUGCAAAGUUUGUUUAUCAAGCCUGGAUUACUGAUCCUAAAACAGCACUCCGACAAAGACACAAAGAGAAAAAAAGGUCUGCAAGAGAAGAACGGAAACGAAGGCGGAAAGGAUCCAAGGAGGGUCCUGUGGAAUGGGAAGACCGGGAGGAUGAACCAAUCAAAAAGAAAUCCGAUGGACCAGAUAAUAUCAUCAAGAGGAUAUUUAAUAUUUUGAAAUUUACCUGGGUCCUAUUUCUGGCAACAGUGGACAGUUUCACUACUUGGCUUAACUCCAUUUCAAGGGAGCAUAUUGAUAUAUCUACAGUUCUGAGAAUUGAACGAUGCAUGCUGACCAGAGAAAUUAAGAAGGGCAAUGUUCCAACUCGGGAGAGCAUCCACAUGUACUAUCAGAACCACAUCAUGAACCUUUCCAGAGAGUCGGGACUGGACACCAUUGACGAGCAUCCCGGAGCUGCUUCAGGUGCACAGACAGCCCACAGGAUGGAUAGUUUAGAUUCACAUGACAGUAUCUCCAGCUGCUACACUGAAGCAACCAUGCUGUUCUCAAGGCAGUCCACCCUUGAUGAUUUAGAUGGACAAGAAAUUCCUAAAACAAGCGAGCGUGCUCGGCCUAGGCUCCGUAAAAUGCUCAGCAUGGAUAUGUCCUCCUCAUCAGCUGACAGUGGCAGUUUAGCAUCAAGCGAGCCCACGCAGUGUACCAUGCUGUACUCACGCCAGGGGACCACUGAGACCAUCGAGGAGGUGGAGGCUGAGCAGGAGGAGGAGGCAGGGAGCACGGCGCCUGAGCCCAGGGAGGCCAAGGAGUACGAGGCCACUGGGUACGAUGUGGGAGCCAUGGGUGCCGAGGAGGCCAGCCUCACCCCAGAGGAAGAGCUGACACAGUUCUCCACCUUGGACGGGGAUGUGGAGGCCCCACCCUCCUACAGCAAGGCUGUGAGCUUCGAGCAUCUGUCCUUCGGCUCGCAGGACGACUCUGCAGGCAAGAACCGUAUGGCAGUCAGCCCGGACGACAGCCGCACCGACAAGCUGGGGUCCAGCAUCUUACCUCCCCUGACCCAUGAGCUGACGGCCAGCGAGCUGCUGCUGAAAAAGAUGUUUCACGACGAUGAGCUUGAAGAGUCAGAGAAAUUCUACGUGGGGCAGCCCCGAUUUCUGCUGCUCUUCUAUGCCAUGUACAAUACCCUGGUGGCCCGCUCGGAGAUGGUGUGCUACUUCGUGAUCAUCCUCAACCACAUGGUCUCUGCCUCCAUGAUCACGCUCCUGCUUCCCAUCCUCAUCUUCCUCUGGGCCAUGUUGUCCGUCCCCAGGCCCAGCCGCCGGUUCUGGAUGAUGGCCAUCGUCUAUACUGAGGUGGCAAUUGUAGUCAAGUAUUUCUUCCAAUUUGGGUUCUUUCCCUGGAAUAAGAAUGUGGAGGUGAACAAAGAUAAACCGUAUCACCCCCCAAACAUCAUAGGAGUGGAAAAGAAGGAAGGUUAUGUUCUCUAUGACCUCAUCCAGCUCCUGGCUCUGUUCUUUCAUCGAUCAAUUUUGAAGUGCCAUGGCUUAUGGGAUGAAGAUGACAUGACUGAAAGUGGCAUGGCCAGGGAGGAAUCAGAUGAUGAGCUCUCCCUCGGUCAUGGCAGGAGGGACUCCUCCGAUUCUCUCAAGUCCAUCAACCUGGCCGCGUCUGUGGAGUCAGUGCAUGUGACCUUCCCGGAGCAGCAGACAGCUGUCCGGAGGAAGCGCUCCGGCAGCAGCUCCGAGCCAUCCCAGAGAUCCAGCUUUUCUUCAAACAGAUCCCAAAGAGGCAGCACAAGCACCCGAAACAGCAGUCAAAAAGGAAGCAGUGUUUUGAGUAUUAAGCAAAAAGGCAAAAGGGAACUUUAUAUGGAAAAGCUUCAAGAACAUUUAAUCAAAGCAAAAGCCUUUACCAUAAAGAAGACGCUGGAGAUCUAUGUGCCCAUCAAACAGUUCUUUUACAACCUCAUCCACCCGGAGUAUAGCGCCGUGACUGACGUGUAUGUACUCAUGUUCCUGGCUGACACUGUGGACUUCAUCAUCAUUGUCUUCGGCUUUUGGGCCUUUGGGAAACACUCAGCAGCUGCAGACAUCACCUCUUCACUGUCAGAGGACCAGGUCCCGGGGCCGUUUUUGGUGAUGGUCCUCAUUCAGUUUGGAACCAUGGUGGUGGACCGAGCCCUCUACCUCAGGAAGACUGUACUGGGAAAGGUCAUCUUCCAGGUCAUUCUUGUGUUCGGAAUUCACUUCUGGAUGUUCUUCAUCUUACCUGGUGUGACUGAGAGGAAAUUCAGCCAGAACCUGGUUGCCCAGCUUUGGUACUUUGUGAAAUGUGUUUACUUCGGGUUGUCUGCUUACCAGAUCCGUUGUGGCUACCCAACGCGAGUCCUGGGGAACUUCCUCACCAAGAGCUACAAUUACGUCAACCUCUUCUUAUUCCAAGGGUUUCGCCUCGUGCCCUUUUUGACUGAGCUGAGGGCAGUGAUGGACUGGGUGUGGACGGACACAACUUUGAGCCUGUCCAGCUGGAUCUGUGUGGAGGACAUCUAUGCUCACAUAUUCAUCCUGAAGUGUUGGCGGGAGUCGGAGAAGAGAUACCCUCAGCCACGGGGCCAGAAGAAGAAGAAAGUGGUGAAGUAUGGCAUGGGAGGAAUGAUCAUCGUCCUGCUCAUCUGCAUUGUCUGGUUUCCUCUUCUCUUCAUGUCUUUGAUCAAAUCUGUGGCUGGGGUCAUCAACCAGCCCCUGGACGUCUCCGUCACAAUUACCCUGGGAGGGUAUCAGCCUAUUUUCACAAUGAGUGCCCAACAAAGCCAGUUGAAAGUUAUGGACCAGCAGAGCUUUAACAAAUUUAUACAAGCUUUUUCUAGGGACACCGGUGCUAUGCAAUUUCUGGAAAAUUAUGAAAAAGAAGACAUAACAGUAGCAGAACUGGAAGGAAACUCAAAUUCUUUGUGGACCAUCAGCCCACCCAGUAAGCAGAAAAUGAUACACGAACUCCUGGACCCCAAUAGUAGCUUCUCUGUUGUUUUUUCAUGGAGUAUUCAGAGAAACUUAAGUCUGGGUGCAAAAUCGGAAAUAGCAACAGAUAAGCUUUCUUUUCCUCUUAAAAAUAUUACUCGAAAGAAUAUCGCUAAAAUGAUAGCAGGCAACAGCACAGAAAGUUCAAAAACACCAGUGACCAUAGAAAAGAUUUAUCCAUAUUAUGUGAAAGCACCUAGUGAUUCUAACUCAAAACCUAUAAAGCAACUUUUAUCUGAAAAUAAUUUCAUGGAUAUUACCAUCAUUUUGUCCAGAGACAAUACAACUAAAUAUAACAGUGAGUGGUGGGUUCUCAACCUGACUGGAAACAGAAUAUACAAUCCGAACUCUCAGGCCCUGGAACUGGUGGUCUUCAAUGACAAAGUCAGUCCCCCAAGUCUGGGGUUCCUGGCUGGCUAUGGUAUUAUGGGAUUAUAUGCUUCAGUUGUCCUUGUGAUUGGGAAAUUUGUCCGUGAAUUCUUCAGUGGGAUUUCUCACUCCAUCAUGUUUGAAGAGCUUCCAAAUGUGGAUCGAAUUUUGAAGUUGUGCACAGAUAUUUUUUUAGUUCGAGAGACAGGAGAACUGGAGCUAGAAGAAGAUCUCUAUGCCAAAUUAAUAUUCCUAUAUCGCUCACCAGAGACAAUGAUCAAAUGGACUAGAGAAAAAACAAAUUGAAACCUUAGAACACAGACUGCAAAUAAUGUUAACAUUUGAAUUUUUUUUAAAAGCACAAUAUUCUCAUAAGAGCUAAGCAUUUCUAGUUCGACGGAAAUGGUUUGUUUCUCUUCUGAUAGGUAGACAAAAGGAGCUGAUAUCCUUCUGCAGUAAAAGCUACCUUGCAAGUUAAGGCACUGUUGAAAAUGUUAUUUGUAACUCCAUUUCUCUGAAAUCAGGGCUACUUGCUUUAUGUUUUAGUCAACAGUGUCUCGCAUUCUGAUUGAUCAUGUGAAGGAAUCAUUUAUGGGCCCCGUCCCUAAGAGAAACAGAAGAGGAGUCAGAAAGAAAGAUGCCUGUGUUUUCCUCUGUGGGGCCCGUGCACUUCCUGGAGAGAUGCUACAAUGCAAUAUACAGCGCUCCAUCCCCACUGGGGAAGCUGCUGUGAUGAGACUAGAUGAGCCUUCAACACACUCAGAAAAUGCAACAGCAAUAGGGGGCAGACAGCUCCUACCUGUGUUUCUAGGAGCAAAAGAGAGGGAACUAAUUGCCCGUGAAGACGCCAGUGGAAGGAUCAGCCUCAUUCUAAGCAAAAACAUAGUAUUAGUGAUACUCUUACUGCCUUAUCUUAACCAAGGACUAAUAGGAUACCUUUCCAUUAAACACCAGUGACUUCUCAGGAAAAAAAAAAAAAAGGAGCAAAACAAAUGAUGUGUACACCUGCUUUGUUAUGGUCCACCAGUGACCAGCUUCAAUGAGGGGAACCAUUCUGGAGGGCUGCGGUCUCCUGUGCAAACAGACAUGAGGCAGAAGAGUAAAAAGACCAACCCAGUGGGACCUAGAAUACUUUGUAACUCUUUAAUAACUGAGGUCAGGACCGCUCUUCUGCCUUCCCCUUCCCUUAACGUGCUUUUUCCCAUUUCCAUGAUUUAAGGCAAUGGUUUUUCCAGUAUGUGACAUUUUCCUUCCUGUUUUUCAGGUAUAUCAAAGAGUUUACAUAUUCCAAUUCACAUUUUUACAUCUGAGACGGGUUUUUUAAGUUCAUAAUUAUGAAAGAAAUAUGUAUAUUGAGCUUGGGGAAAUAAAAAUGGCCUUUUCUUAAAUUAUUAUUAUUGGUAAUACAACCUCUUCAUUAAAUAACAAUGUAGCAUGAAAAAUUUAUGAUUGAAAUGUAGUUUUCAUUCCAUAUUAAGAUACAGUUUCUGAGAAGAAUCAUUGAAUGGACUAGAAUAUGUCAAAAAUUGAUCCUGUGUAGUUUGGGUUCAGGGCUGACUUAAAAUAAAGCACAUCCUGCAAAGUCA